ACUCCGGACUUUGGCCUUAGCAGUAGUUAGUGUGGGAGGCUGGGAAGACUGGGAGCAGUCUCUUAAACAAAAGCAAAAGAAUAAGCUUCGGGCGCUGUAGUACCUGCCAGCUUUCGCCACAGGAGCCUAGGCUGCCACCUGUAGGUCACUUGGGCUCCAGCUAUGUGGCUGCCUCUUCUGCUGGGUGCCUUACUCUGGGCAGUGCUGUGGUUGCUCAGGGACCGGCAGAGCCUGCCCGCCAGCAAUGCCUUUGUCUUCAUCACCGGCUGUGACUCAGGCUUUGGGCGCCUUCUGGCACUGCAGCUGGACCAGAGAGGCUUCCGAGUCCUGGCCAGCUGCCUGACCCCCUCCGGGGCCGAGGACCUGCAGCGGGUGGCCUCCUCCCGCCUCCACACCACCCUGUUGGAUAUCACUGAUCCCCAGAGCGUCCAGCAGGCAGCCAAGUGGGUGGAGAUGCACGUUAAGGAAGCAGGGCUUUUUGGUCUGGUGAAUAAUGCUGGUGUGGCUGGUAUCAUCGGACCCACACCAUGGCUGACCCGGGACGAUUUCCAGCGGGUGCUGAAUGUGAACACAAUGGGUCCCAUCGGGGUCACCCUUGCCCUGCUGCCUCUGCUGCAGCAAGCCCGGGGCCGGGUGAUCAACAUCACCAGCGUCCUGGGUCGCCUGGCAGCCAAUGGUGGGGGCUACUGUGUCUCCAAAUUUGGCCUGGAGGCCUUCUCUGACAGCCUGAGGCGGGAUGUAGCUCAUUUUGGGAUACGAGUCUCCAUCGUGGAGCCUGGCUUCUUCCGAACCCCUGUGACCAACCUGGAGAGUCUGGAGAAAACCCUGCAGGCCUGCUGGGCACGGCUGCCUCCUGCCACACAGGCCCACUAUGGGGGGGCCUUCCUCACCAAGUACCUGAAAAUGCAACAGCGCAUCAUGAACCUGAUCUGUGACCCGGACCUAACCAAGGUGAGCCGAUGCCUGGAGCAUGCCCUGACUGCUCGACACCCCCGAACCCGCUACAGCCCAGGUUGGGAUGCCAAGCUGCUCUGGCUGCCUGCCUCCUACCUGCCAGCCAGCCUGGUGGAUGCUGUGCUCACCUGGGUCCUUCCCAAGCCUGCCCAAGCAGUCUACUGAAUCCAGCCUUCCAGCAAGAGAUUGUUUUUCAAGGACAAGGACUUUGAUUUAUUUCUGCCCCCACCCUGGUACUGCCUGGUGCCUGCCACAAAAUAAGCACUAACAAAAGUGUAUUGUUUAAAAAAUAAAAAGAAGGUGGGCAGAAAUGUGCCCAGUGGAA